AGUCUGCGGUGGGCUAGCGGACGGUCCGGCUUCCGGCGGCCGUUUCUGUCUCUUGCUGGCUGUCUCGCUGAGUCGCGGCCGCCUUCUCAUCGCUCCUGGAAGGUCCCGAGCGCGACACCAUGUCGGAGCCCGGGGGCGGCGGCGGCGAGGACGGCUCGGCCGGAUUGGAAGUGUCGGCCGUGCAGAAUGUGGCGGACGUGUCGGUGCUGCAGAAGCACCUGCGCAAGCUGGUGCCGCUGCUGCUGGAGGACGGCGGCGAGGCGCCGGCCGCGCUGGAGGCGGCGCUGGAGGAGAAGAGCGCCCUGGAGCAGAUGCGCAAGUUCCUUUCGGACCCGCAGGUCCACACGGUGCUGGUGGAGCGCUCCACGCUCAAAGAGGACGUCGGUGAUGAAGGAGAAGAAGAAAAAGAAUUCAUUUCCUAUAACAUCAACAUAGACAUUCAUUAUGGGGUUAAAUCCAAUAGCUUGGCAUUCAUUAAACGUACUCCCGUGAUUGAUGCAGAUAAACCCGUGUCUUCUCAGCUCCGGGUCCUUACACUCAGUGAAGACUCGCCCUACGAAACUUUGCAUUCUUUCAUUAGCAAUGCAGUGGCUCCUUUUUUUAAGUCCUACAUUAGAGAGUCUGGCAAGGCAGACAGGGAUGGUGAUAAAAUGGCUCCUUCAGUUGAAAAGAAGAUUGCAGAACUCGAAAUGGGACUCCUUCACUUGCAGCAAAAUAUUGAAAUUCCGGAGAUCAGCCUGCCGAUUCAUCCAAUGAUCACAAAUGUUGCAAAACAGUGUUAUGAGCGUGGAGAAAAGCCAAAAGUUACAGACUUUGGUGAUAAGGUUGAAGACCCAACAUUUCUUAAUCAGUUACAAUCUGGAGUUAACCGCUGGAUCCGAGAAAUUCAAAAAGUGACCAAACUGGAUCGAGAUCCUGCAUCAGGAACUGCCUUACAGGAAAUUAGUUUUUGGCUAAACUUGGAACGUGCGUUAUACCGCAUCCAGGAGAAACGGGAGAGCCCGGAAGUUCUCCUGACUCUGGAUAUCUUGAAACAUGGCAAGCGCUUCCAUGCCACCGUCAGUUUUGACACUGACACAGGUCUAAAACAGGCUUUGGAAACUGUGAAUGACUACAAUCCUCUGAUGAAAGAUUUCCCUCUGAAUGAUUUGCUGUCUGCCACGGAGCUGGACAAAAUAAGACAGGCGCUUGUUGCCAUUUUCACACAUUUGAGAAAGAUCCGAAACACAAAAUAUCCUAUUCAGAGGGCACUGCGUUUGGUGGAGGCAAUUUCAAGAGACUUGAGUUCUCAAUUACUCAAAGUAUUGGGCACUAGGAAAUUGAUGCAUGUUGCUUAUGAAGAAUUUGAAAAAGUUAUGGUAGCAUGCUUUGAAGUUUUUCAGACUUGGGAUGAUGAGUAUGAGAAACUUCAGGUAUUGUUGAGAGACAUCGUCAAAAGAAAAAGGGAAGAAAAUCUGAAGAUGGUGUGGCGUAUCAACCCUGCCCACAGGAAGCUGCAGGCCCGCCUUGACCAGAUGAGAAAAUUUAGACGCCAGCAUGAACAGCUAAGAGCUGUUAUCGUCAGGGUCCUGAGGCCACAGGUCACGGCAGUUGCACAACAGAAUCAAGGAGAGGUCCCUGAACCCCAAGAUAUGAAAGUGGCUGAGGUUCUCUUUGAUGCUGCAGAUGCAAAUGCCAUUGAGGAAGUAAACCUUGCUUAUGAGAACGUCAAGGAAGUGGAUGGACUGGAUGUUUCCAAAGAGGGCACGGAAGCCUGGGAGGCUGCUAUGAAGAGGUACGAUGAGAGGAUCGACAGAGUGGAGACCCGGAUCACCGCUCGCCUUCGGGAUCAGCUUGGCACAGCCAAGAAUGCCAACGAGAUGUUUAGGAUUUUCUCCAGGUUUAAUGCACUGUUUGUCAGGCCUCACAUCCGUGGGGCCAUUCGCGAAUACCAGACCCAGCUGAUCCAGCGCGUGAAAGAUGACAUUGAGUCUCUUCACGACAAGUUCAAGGUCCAGUACCCACAGAGUCAGGCUUGUAAGAUGAGUCACGUUCGUGACUUGCCCCCUGUGUCAGGGUCUAUCAUCUGGGCUAAACAGAUCGACAGGCAGCUGACGGCCUACAUGAAGCGGGUGGAAGAUGUCCUUGGCAAGGGCUGGGAGAAUCACGUGGAGGGGCAGAAGCUGAAGCAGGAUGGAGACAGCUUCCGCAUGAAGCUCAACACGCAGGAGAUCUUUGAUGACUGGGCAAGGAAGGUGCAGCAGCGCAACCUCGGUGUCUCGGGGCGCAUUUUCACCAUCGAAAGUACUCGGGUUCGGGGCCGAACUGGAAAUGUGCUUAAGCUGAAAGUUAACUUUCUUCCUGAGAUUAUCACACUAUCCAAAGAAGUCCGGAACCUCAAAUGGCUUGGUUUCCGCGUCCCACUGGCGAUUGUGAACAAAGCCCAUCAAGCAAACCAGCUUUACCCGUUUGCCAUCUCACUGAUCGAGAGCGUUCGUACCUAUGAACGGACCUGCGAGAAGGUGGAGGAGCGGAACACCAUUUCCCUUUUGGUGGCUGGCUUGAAAAAGGAAGUGCAGGCCCUGAUCGCAGAAGGCAUUGCGUUGGUGUGGGAGUCCUACAAACUUGACCCAUAUGUACAGCGCUUAGCAGAGACUGUCUUCAACUUCCAAGAAAAGGUGGAUGAUCUGCUGAUCAUUGAAGAAAAAAUAGACCUAGAAGUCCGUUCCUUGGAAACUUGUAUGUAUGACCAUAAGACAUUCUCGGAAAUCUUGAACAGAGUCCAGAAAGCAGUGGAUGACUUAAAUCUGCACUCCUAUUCCAAUUUGCCCAUCUGGGUCAACAAGCUUGACAUGGAGAUUGAAAGAAUAUUGGGCGUCCGUCUGCAAGCUGGCCUGAGAGCUUGGACGCAGGUUCUUCUUGGACAAGCUGAAGAUAAAGCAGAAGUUGACAUGGACACAGAUGCUCCACAAGUUAGUCACAAGCCUGGUGGAGAGCCAAAGAUCAAAAAUGUCGUUCAUGAGCUAAGAAUAACCAAUCAGGUAAUCUACUUGAAUCCACCAAUUGAAGAGUGCAGAUACAAGCUGUAUCAGGAAAUGUUUGCCUGGAAGAUGGUUGUACUGUCUCUCCCCAGGAUCCAGAGUCAGAGGUACCAGGUGGGUGUACAUUACGAAUUGACUGAGGAAGAGAAAUUCUAUCGGAAUGCUUUAACACGGAUGCCUGAUGGCCCUGUUGCCCUGGAAGAGUCGUAUUCUGCUGUCAUGGGCAUUGUAUCUGAAGUUGAACAGUAUGUCAAGGUUUGGCUUCAGUAUCAGUGUUUAUGGGAUAUGCAAGCUGAAAACAUCUAUAACAGACUUGGAGAAGAUCUCAACAAAUGGCAGGCUCUCCUGGUCCAAAUAAGGAAGGCCAGAGGAACCUUUGACAAUGCAGAAACCAAGAAAGAGUUUGGACCAGUAGUUAUAGAUUAUGGCAAGGUACAAUCUAAGGUGAACUUGAAAUAUGACUCUUGGCAUAAGGAGGUUCUUAGCAAAUUUGGGCAGAUGCUAGGAUCAAACAUGACGGAAUUCCAUUCCCAGAUCUCAAAGUCCCGCCAAGAGUUGGAGCAGCACUCAGUAGACACGGCCAGCACCUCCGAUGCAGUGACCUUCAUCACCUAUGUGCAGUCUUUGAAACGGAAGAUCAAGCAGUUUGAGAAGCAAGUUGAGCUCUACCGCAAUGGCCAGCGCUUACUGGAAAAGCAAAGGUUCCAGUUCCCACCUUCCUGGCUUUAUAUUGACAACAUCGAGGGAGAGUGGGGAGCCUUCAAUGACAUCAUGCGGCGAAAGGACUCUGCCAUUCAGCAGCAGGUGGCAAACCUGCAAAUGAAGAUUGUCCAGGAGGAUCGGGCCGUGGAAAGCCGCACCACCGACCUGCUGACUGACUGGGAGAAGACCAAGCCUGUCACGGGCAACCUUCGCCCAGAAGAGGCACUUCAGGCUCUCACCAUAUAUGAGGGGAAGUUUGGUAGGCUGAAGGACGACAGAGAGAAGUGUGCAAAGGCCAAGGAGGCGCUGGAAUUGACAGAUACUGGGCUUCUCAGUGGCAGUGAAGAGCGCGUGCAGGUGGCCUUAGAAGAAUUACAGGACCUCAAAGGCGUUUGGUCAGAACUUUCUAAGGUUUGGGAGCAAAUCGAUCAGAUGAAGGAGCAACCCUGGGUUUCAGUACAGCCUCGAAAGCUUCGACAAAAUUUGGAUGCCCUCCUGAACCAGCUGAAAAGCUUCCCUGCCCGGUUGCGACAGUAUGCGUCCUAUGAGUUUGUUCAGAGGCUUCUGAAAGGUUACAUGAAGAUAAAUAUGCUGGUGAUUGAACUGAAAUCCGAAGCACUUAAAGACCGCCAUUGGAAACAGCUCAUGAAAAGGCUUCACGUUAAUUGGGUUGUUUCUGAGCUAACCCUUGGCCAAAUCUGGGAUGUUGACUUGCAGAAAAAUGAAGCGAUUGUCAAGGAUGUACUGCUUGUGGCACAAGGGGAGAUGGCUUUGGAAGAAUUUUUGAAGCAGAUAAGAGAAGUGUGGAAUACUUAUGAACUAGACUUGGUUAAUUAUCAGAACAAGUGCCGCUUGAUCCGUGGCUGGGAUGACCUCUUCAACAAGGUCAAAGAACACAUCAACAGCGUCUCGGCCAUGAAGCUCUCUCCGUAUUACAAGGUUUUUGAAGAGGAUGCUCUCAGCUGGGAAGAUAAGCUGAACAGGAUCAUGGCUCUCUUUGAUGUGUGGAUUGAUGUGCAGAGGCGGUGGGUCUACCUGGAAGGUAUCUUCACAGGCAGUGCAGAUAUCAAGCACCUGCUGCCAGUGGAAACCCAGCGGUUUCAGAGCAUCAGCACUGAGUUUUUGGCUCUAAUGAAAAAAGUGUCCAAGUCUCCCCUUGUUAUGGAUGUUCUGAACAUCCAGGGAGUACAGAGGUCUCUGGAAAGAUUGGCAGACCUGCUAGGAAAGAUCCAGAAAGCAUUGGGAGAAUAUCUGGAAAGAGAGCGGUCAUCUUUCCCCAGGUUCUAUUUUGUGGGUGAUGAAGAUUUGCUUGAAAUCAUUGGAAACAGCAAGAAUGUCGCUAAAUUACAGAAACACUUCAAGAAGAUGUUUGCUGGAGUUUCGAGCAUCAUCCUGAACGAGGAUAACUCUGUUGUUUUGGGUAUUUCAUCUCGGGAAGGAGAGGAGGUUAUGUUUAAAACUCCUGUGUCAAUUACUGAACAUCCCAAAAUCAAUGAGUGGCUCACAUUGGUAGAAAAGGAGAUGAGAGUCACCCUGGCCAAACUGCUUGCUGAGUCUGUUACGGAAGUUGAGAUUUUUGGUAAAGCAACUUCAAUUGACCCAAAUACCUACAUCACUUGGAUUGAUAAAUACCAGGCCCAGCUUGUGGUUUUGUCAGCCCAGAUAGCCUGGUCUGAGAACGUGGAGACCGCACUGAGCAGCAUGGGCGGAGGUGGAGAUGCCGCGCCCUUGCACUCUGUGCUGAGCAAUGUGGAGGUCACCCUCAAUGUGUUAGCAGACUCUGUCCUCAUGGAGCAGCCCCCACUCCGAAGGCGGAAGCUAGAACACUUGAUUACAGAGUUGGUUCACCAGAGAGAUGUUACAAGGUCCUUGAUCAAAAGCAAGAUUGACAACGCCAAAUCUUUUGAAUGGCUCAGCCAGAUGCGAUUUUACUUUGACCCUAAGCAAACUGAUGUGUUACAGCAGUUGUCAAUUCAAAUGGCAAAUGCCAAAUUUAACUAUGGCUUUGAGUACCUGGGUGUUCAGGACAAACUGGUCCAGACCCCCCUCACUGACCGCUGCUAUUUGACAAUGACACAAGCCUUGGAGGCCAGGCUGGGGGGUUCCCCAUUUGGACCUGCUGGAACUGGGAAAACAGAGUCUGUCAAAGCUCUUGGCCAUCAGCUUGGACGGUUUGUUUUAGUUUUCAACUGUGAUGAAACCUUUGAUUUCCAGGCAAUGGGCCGGAUCUUUGUGGGCCUUUGCCAGGUGGGUGCCUGGGGCUGCUUUGACGAGUUCAACCGCCUGGAGGAGCGGAUGCUCUCGGCUGUGUCCCAGCAGGUGCAGUGCAUACAGGAAGCACUGCGUGAACAUUCCAACCCCAACUACGACAAGACCUCUGCCCCCAUUACUUGUGAGCUGCUGAACAAACAAGUCAAGGUGAGCCCGGACAUGGCCAUCUUCAUCACCAUGAACCCUGGCUACGCGGGCCGGUCUAACCUUCCUGACAACUUGAAGAAGCUGUUCCGGAGCUUGGCCAUGACCAAGCCCGACCGGCAGUUAAUCGCCCAGGUCAUGCUGUACUCACAGGGUUUCCGCACUGCUGAAGUGCUUGCCAACAAAAUCGUCCCGUUUUUUAAACUAUGCGAUGAGCAGCUCUCUUCCCAAAGCCAUUAUGACUUCGGUCUUCGGGCUUUGAAGAGUGUGCUGGUGAGUGCAGGCAAUGUGAAGAGAGAGAGAAUCCAGAAGAUAAAGAGGGAGAAAGAGGAACGAGGGGAAGCAGUUGAUGAAGGAGAAAUUGCUGAAAAUCUCCCUGAACAAGAGAUUCUGAUACAGAGCGUCUGUGAGACGAUGGUGCCAAAGCUGGUGGCAGAGGACAUCCCGCUGCUCUUCAGCCUCCUGUCGGACGUGUUCCCUGGAGUCCAGUAUCACAGGGGUGAGAUGACUGCCCUUCGAGAGGAGCUGAAGAAAGUGUGUCAGGAGAUGUAUUUGACAUAUGGAGAUGGAGAAGAAGUUGGUGGAAUGUGGGUUGAAAAGGUUCUCCAGCUCUAUCAGAUCACCCAGAUCAAUCAUGGCCUGAUGAUGGUGGGGCCCUCGGGAAGUGGGAAGAGCAUGGCCUGGCGUGUCCUGCUGAAGGCAUUGGAGAGACUCGAGGGUGUGGAAGGUGUGGCCCAUAUCAUCGACCCCAAGGCCAUCAGCAAAGACCACCUCUACGGAACCCUGGACCCCAACACCAGGGAAUGGACAGAUGGGCUCUUCACACACGUGCUGAGAAAGAUCAUCGACAGCGUGAGAGGCGAGCUGCAGAAGCGCCAGUGGAUCGUCUUCGAUGGCGAUGUGGAUCCAGAGUGGGUUGAGAACUUGAACUCAGUGCUGGAUGACAAUAAGCUCCUAACUUUGCCCAAUGGAGAGCGCCUCAGUCUUCCACCCAAUGUGAGAAUAAUGUUUGAGGUACAGGACUUGAAAUACGCGACCUUGGCCACAGUGUCGCGCUGCGGCAUGGUCUGGUUCAGUGAGGAUGUGCUGAGCACCGACAUGAUCUUCAACAACUUCCUGGCCAGGCUGCGCAGCAUCCCGCUGGAUGAAGGGGAGGAUGAGGCACAGCGGCGGCGUAAGGGCAAAGAGGAUGAGGGGGAGGAGGCCGCUUCCCCCAUGCUGCAGAUCCAAAGAGAUGCAGCUACGAUCAUGCAACCGUACUUCACGUCCAACGGCCUGGUCACCAAGGCGCUAGAGCACGCCUUCCAGCUGGAGCACAUCAUGGACCUAACACGCCUGCGCUGCCUGGGCUCGCUCUUCUCCAUGCUGCACCAGGCCUGCCGCAACGUGGCGCAGUAUAACGCCAACCAUCCCGACUUCCCCAUGCAGAUCGAGCAGCUGGAGCGCUACAUUCAGCGAUAUCUGGUUUAUGCCAUACUCUGGUCCCUGUCUGGAGACAGCCGGCUAAAAAUGAGAGCAGAGCUGGGUGAAUACAUCAGAAGAAUCACGACCGUGCCUCUGCCCACUGCGCCCAACAUACCCAUUAUCGAUUAUGAGGUGUCCAUCAGCGGAGAAUGGUCUCCGUGGCAGGCCAAGGUGCCUCAGAUUGAAGUGGAGACGCACAAGGUGGCAGCCCCUGAUGUCGUCGUGCCAACGCUGGACACAGUCCGCCACGAAGCCCUCUUGUACACUUGGCUGGCCGAACACAAGCCCCUGGUCUUGUGUGGCCCUCCUGGGUCUGGCAAGACCAUGACACUCUUCAGCGCCCUCCGGGCCUUGCCUGACAUGGAGGUGGUGGGUCUCAACUUCUCCAGUGCUACUACUCCAGAGCUGCUUCUGAAGACUUUUGAUCACUACUGCGAGUACAGGCGCACACCUAAUGGGGUGGUUUUGGCUCCUGUUCAACUUGGAAAGUGGCUGGUGUUGUUCUGUGAUGAAAUCAACUUGCCAGAUAUGGAUAAAUAUGGGACCCAGAGGGUCAUAUCCUUCAUCAGACAGAUGGUGGAGCACGGAGGCUUUUACCGUACCUCAGAUCAAACAUGGGUGAAGCUGGAGAGAAUCCAGUUUGUUGGGGCUUGUAAUCCCCCCACAGACCCUGGAAGAAAGCCCCUCUCACACAGGUUCCUGCGCCACGUGCCUGUCGUGUAUGUGGAUUACCCGGGCCCCGCCUCCCUCACACAGAUCUACGGCACCUUCAACCGCGCCAUGCUGAGGCUCAUUCCAUCCCUGCGGACGUAUGCAGAGCCGCUCACUGCUGCCAUGGUGGAGUUCUACACCAUGUCUCAGGAGAGAUUCACCCAGGAUACACAACCUCACUAUAUCUAUUCACCCCGUGAAAUGACUAGGUGGGUGAGAGGCAUCUUUGAAGCGCUGAGACCUCUGGAGACCCUGCCUGUUGAAGGCCUCAUUCGGAUUUGGGCACAUGAAGCUCUGCGUCUCUUCCAAGAUAGACUCGUAGAGGAUGAGGAGAGGCGUUGGACUGAUGAGAACAUCGACACGGUUGCUCUGAAGCACUUCCCUAACAUCGACAGAGAGAAGGCAAUGAGCCGACCCAUCUUGUACAGCAACUGGCUGUCAAAGGAUUACAUCCCAGUAGACCAAGAAGAGUUAAGAGAUUAUGUCAAAGCUAGGCUGAAGGUCUUUUAUGAAGAAGAACUUGAUGUUCCGCUGGUGCUGUUUAAUGAAGUCCUAGACCACGUGCUGAGGAUUGACAGAAUAUUCCGUCAACCUCAAGGCCACUUGCUUCUGAUUGGUGUUAGUGGAGCAGGAAAAACUACCCUGUCUCGUUUCGUCGCCUGGAUGAACGGUUUGAGUGUGUACCAGAUUAAGGUCCAUAGGAAGUACACAGGGGAAGACUUUGAUGAAGAUCUACGGACAGUGUUGAGACGUUCUGGCUGUAAAAAUGAAAAGAUAGCAUUUAUAAUGGAUGAAUCUAAUGUGUUAGAUUCUGGAUUCCUGGAGCGAAUGAAUACCCUUCUGGCCAAUGGAGAGGUGCCUGGUCUCUUUGAAGGAGACGAGUAUGCCACCUUGAUGACGCAGUGCAAAGAGGGGGCACAGAAGGAAGGCCUGAUGCUGGACUCGCACGAGGAGCUCUACAAGUGGUUCACUAGCCAGGUUAUCCGCAACCUCCACGUCGUGUUCACCAUGAACCCGUCCUCGGAGGGACUCAAGGACCGGGCAGCUACAUCACCAGCACUUUUCAACAGGUGUGUGUUGAAUUGGUUUGGAGACUGGUCCACCGAAGCACUGUAUCAGGUUGGCAAAGAAUUCACAAGUAAGAUGGAUCUGGAGAAGCCAAAUUACAUCGUGCCUGAUUACAUGCCAGUUGUGUAUGAUAAGCUGCCGCAGCCACCAUCCCAUCGGGAAGCCAUUGUGAACAGCUGUGUGUUUGUUCAUCAGACUCUUCACCAGGCGAAUGCUCGGCUAGCAAAGCGAGGCGGCAGAACGAUGGCCAUCACCCCUCGCCACUACCUGGACUUCAUCAAUCACUAUGCCAACCUGUUCCACGAGAAGCGGAGCGAGCUGGAGGAGCAGCAGAUGCACUUGAACGUGGGGCUCAGGAAGAUCAAAGAGACAGUCGACCAGGUAGAAGAACUGCGUCGUGACUUGAGGAUAAAGAGCCAAGAGCUGGAGGUGAAGAAUGCAGCAGCCAAUGACAAGCUGAAAAAGAUGGUGAAAGACCAGCAGGAGGCUGAAAAGAAGAAGGUUAUGAGCCAAGAAAUCCAGGAACAGCUGCAUAAGCAGCAGGAGGUAAUUGCAGACAAACAGAUGAGUGUCAAAGAAGAUCUUGAUAAGGUGGAACCUGCCGUCAUUGAGGCCCAGAAUGCUGUGAAGUCGAUCAAGAAGCAGCACCUGGUGGAGGUGAGGUCCAUGGCCAACCCUCCUGCUGCUGUGAAGCUGGCGCUGGAGUCCAUCUGCCUGCUGCUGGGGGAAAGCACCACAGACUGGAAGCAGAUCCGCUCCAUCAUCAUGCGGGAGAACUUCAUCCCCACCAUCGUCAACUUCUCUGCAGAGGAGAUCAGUGACGCCAUAAGGGAGAAGAUGAAGAAAAAUUACAUGUCCAAUCCAAGUUACAAUUAUGAAAUUGUGAAUCGGGCUUCCCUGGCUUGCGGCCCUAUGGUGAAAUGGGCAAUUGCACAGCUUAACUAUGCAGACAUGUUAAAGAGAGUGGAGCCCCUACGCAAUGAGCUGCAGAAGCUGGAAGAUGACGCCAAGGACAACCAGCAGAAGGCCAACGAGGUGGAGCAGAUGAUCCGAGACCUGGAAGCCAGCAUCGCCCGCUACAAGGAGGAAUACGCCGUCCUGAUCUCAGAGGCCCAGGCCAUCAAGGCAGACCUGGCAGCUGUCGAGGCAAAAGUAAACCGGAGCACUGCUCUUCUGAAGAGCUUGUCUGCUGAACGUGAACGAUGGGAAAAAACAAGUGAAACUUUCAAAAACCAGAUGUCCACCAUUGCUGGGGACUGUCUCUUGUCAGCUGCGUUCAUUGCCUACGCGGGUUACUUUGACCAGCAGAUGCGUCAGAACUUGUUCACUACCUGGUCCCAUCACCUACAGCAAGCCAACAUCCAGUUCCGUACAGAUAUUGCCAGGACGGAAUACCUUUCCAAUGCUGAUGAGCGUCUUCGCUGGCAGGCCAGCUCCUUGCCUGCUGAUGACCUUUGCACAGAAAAUGCCAUCAUGCUGAAACGAUUCAAUAGGUAUCCGCUGAUCAUUGACCCCUCUGGACAGGCCACAGAAUUCAUUAUGAAUGAAUAUAAGGAUCGUAAGAUCACACGGACCAGCUUCCUGGAUGACGCCUUCAGAAAGAACUUAGAGAGUGCACUGAGAUUCGGUAACCCCCUUCUGGUCCAGGAUGUGGAAAGCUACGAUCCAGUUUUGAACCCGGUGCUGAACCGUGAAGUGCGGCGAACAGGGGGGAGAGUGCUGAUCACUCUCGGGGACCAGGACAUAGACCUGUCGCCAUCGUUUGUCAUCUUCCUGUCCACCCGGGAUCCAACUGUCGAGUUCCCACCAGAUCUCUGUUCCCGGGUUACUUUUGUAAACUUCACAGUUACCCGUAGCAGUUUACAAAGCCAGUGUCUAAAUGAAGUACUUAAAGCAGAAAGACCUGAUGUGGACGAGAAACGAUCUGAUCUUCUUAAACUUCAAGGGGAAUUUCAGCUCCGUUUGCGUCAGCUGGAAAAAUCUCUACUACAAGCUCUGAACGAGGUGAAAGGGCGCAUUUUGGAUGACGACACGAUCAUAACCACUCUGGAGAACCUGAAGAGAGAGGCUGCAGAGGUCACCAGGAAAGUUGAGGAGACGGACAUUGUCAUGCAGGAGGUGGAGACCGUGUCCCAGCAGUACCUCCCGCUCUCCACCGCCUGCAGCAGCAUCUACUUCACCAUGGAGUCCCUCAAGCAGAUACACUUCUUGUACCAGUACUCCCUCCAGUUUUUCCUGGACAUUUAUCACAACGUCCUAUACGAGAACCCGAACCUGAAGGGUGUCACCGACCACACACAGCGCCUGUCCAUUAUAACAAAGGACCUCUUCCAGGUGGCGUUUAACCGAGUGGCUCGAGGCAUGCUGCAUCAGGACCACAUUACCUUUGCCAUGCUGCUGGCAAGAAUCAAACUGAAGGGCACCGUGGGGGAGCCCACCUACGAUGCAGAAUUCCAGCACUUCUUGAGAGGAAAUGAGAUUGUCCUGAGUGCUGGCUCCACCCCCAGGAUCCAGGGCCUGACUGUGGAGCAGGCGGAGGCGGUGGUGAGGCUGAGCUGCCUUCCCGCGUUUAAGGACUUGAUUGCAAAGGUUCAGGCAGACGAGCAAUUUGGCAUCUGGCUGGACAGCAGCUCCCCGGAGCAGACUGUGCCCUACCUCUGGAGUGAAGAAACACCUGCAACACCCAUUGGCCAGGCCAUCCACCGCCUGCUCCUGAUCCAGGCUUUCCGGCCCGAUCGCCUGUUGGCCAUGGCCCACAUGUUUGUUUCAACAAACCUUGGGGAGUCUUUCAUGUCCAUCAUGGAGCAGCCGCUCGACCUGACCCACAUUGUGGGCACAGAGGUGAAGCCCAACACUCCUGUCUUAAUGUGCUCUGUGCCUGGUUAUGAUGCCAGUGGACAUGUCGAGGACCUUGCAGCCGAGCAGAACACGCAGAUCACUUCAAUUGCAAUCGGCUCUGCAGAAGGCUUUAACCAAGCAGAUAAGGCAAUAAACACCGCUGUAAAGUCGGGCAGGUGGGUGAUGCUGAAGAAUGUGCAUCUGGCCCCAGGGUGGCUGAUGCAGCUGGAGAAGAAGUUGCAUUCCCUGCAGCCGCAUGCCUGCUUCCGACUCUUCCUCACCAUGGAGAUCAACCCCAAGGUGCCUGUGAAUCUGCUCCGUGCGGGCCGCAUCUUUGUGUUCGAGCCACCGCCAGGGGUGAAGGCCAACAUGCUGAGGACGUUCAGCAGCAUUCCCGUCUCACGGAUAUGCAAGUCUCCCAACGAGCGUGCCCGCUUGUACUUCCUGCUGGCCUGGUUUCAUGCGAUCAUCCAAGAACGCUUACGAUACGCACCACUGGGGUGGUCAAAGAAGUAUGAAUUUGGAGAGUCUGACCUGCGGUCAGCUUGCGAUACGGUGGACACGUGGCUGGAUGACACGGCCAAGGGCAGGCAGAACAUCUCACCGGAUAAGAUCCCGUGGUCUGCACUAAAGACCUUAAUGGCCCAGUCCAUUUAUGGCGGGCGCGUGGACAACGAGUUUGACCAGCGUCUGCUCAACACCUUCCUGGAGCGCCUGUUCACAACCAGGAGUUUCGACAGUGAGUUUAAGCUGGCAUGCAAGGUCGACGGACAUAAAGACAUUCAAAUGCCAGAUGGCAUCAGGCGAGAGGAGUUUGUGCAGUGGGUGGAGUUGCUCCCCGACACCCAGACGCCCUCCUGGCUGGGCCUGCCCAACAACGCCGAGAGAGUCCUCCUUACCACACAGGGUGUGGACAUGAUCAGUAAAAUGCUGAAGAUGCAGAUGUUGGAGGAUGAGGACGACCUGGCCUACGCAGAGACUGAGAAGAAGACGAGGACAGACUCCACGUCCGACGGGCGCCCUGCCUGGAUGCGGACACUGCACACCACCGCGUCCAACUGGCUGCACCUCAUCCCCCAGACGCUGAGCCACCUCAAGCGCACCGUGGAGAAUAUCAAGGAUCCUUUGUUCAGGUUCUUUGAGAGAGAAGUGAAGAUGGGCGCAAAGCUGCUUCAGGACGUUCGCCAGGACCUUGCAGAUGUCGUCCAGGUGUGCGAAGGAAAGAAGAAGCAGACCAACUACUUGCGCACGCUGAUCAACGAGCUAGUGAAAGGGAUCUUGCCUCGGAGCUGGUCCCACUACACGGUGCCUGCCGGCAUGACCGUCAUCCAGUGGGUGUCCGACUUCAGCGAGAGGAUCAAACAGCUGCAGAACAUCUCACUGGCAGCUGCAUCUGGUGGCGCCAAGGAGCUAAAGAACAUCCACGUGUGCCUGGGUGGCCUGUUCGUGCCUGAGGCGUACAUCACUGCCACCAGGCAGUAUGUGGCCCAGGCCAACAGCUGGUCCCUGGAGGAGCUCUGCCUGGAAGUCAACGUCACCACCUCACAGGGCGCCACCCUUGACGCUUGCAGCUUCGGAGUCACGGGUUUGAAACUUCAAGGGGCCACGUGCAACAACAACAAGCUGUCACUGUCCAAUGCCAUCUCAACCGCCCUUCCCCUGACGCAGCUGCGCUGGGUCAAGCAGACAAACACCGAGAAGAAGGCCAGUGUGGUAACCUUACCUGUCUACCUGAACUUCACCCGUGCAGACCUCAUCUUCACCGUGGACUUCGAAAUUGCUACAAAGGAGGAUCCUCGCAGCUUCUACGAGCGGGGUGUCGCAGUCUUGUGCACAGAGUAAACUUUUCUAGCUGCCCCUUUCUGUAAUAGUGAAAGUUGGUAUUUAACAUUUAUUCAUUUUUAAAAUAUUUGGAAGGUCUGAGCUUGUGAAAAGAAAGUGGUUGGUCUGAGGUUGGAGGAAGCUGAAUGGAAUCUGACGGUUGGGAGUGGUGGAAAUUGGAAGGAUACCAGGAGGUAUUUGGGAAGGCCAAUGGCGUGGCUCCUUUGAGGAAAUAAAACACUAAGCAUGAGCCGGCUCCGCCUCUUCUGUCUCCGCUUUCAUCCCAGGGCACAGAGCCUUGCCUUCCAUGCUGCCCAGGGAGGGCAGCCCACGGCAGCCAUGCCCCUCCCCACCUCGCUUUCAUCAUGAGCUCGCUCCCGAGCGGCCACAGCACUCAUGAAUGAAGACCUUGGGGCCCUUCACAGACACAGAUGCAGCCAGCUGUGGCUCUGAAGGCCCUGGGGCCCGGGCACCAUGGUUCACACCUUUAAUCGCAGCACUUUGGGAGUCUGGGAGUUAAAGACCAGCCUCGGCAACAUAGUGAGACCCCGUCUCUACAGGAAAUUAAAUCAGGUGUGGUGGUGCAUGCCUGUAGUCCCAGCUACUUGAGGGCUGAGGUGGGAGGAUCACCCAAGCCCAAGAGGUCGAGGCUGCAGUGAGCUGUGAUCUCACCACUGCACUCCAGCCUGGGUGACAGAGCAAGACCCUGUCUCAAAAAAAAAAAAAGCUGGGCGUGGUGGCUCAUGCCUGUAAUCCCAGCACUUUGGGAGGCCGAGGCGGGCGGAUCACCAAAUUAGCCGGGCAUGGUGGCACAUGCCUGUAAUCCCAGCUACUCGGGAGGCUGAGGCAGGAGAAUUGCUUGAACCUGGGAGGCGGAGGUUGCAGUGAGCUGAAAAAAAAAAAGGCAGCCCCCAGCCGCUUGUGUUCUUGACCAGGGCCCCAGGACUUGGCUCCUCCAGACAAGGGAGUUUUGUGCUGUAGAUGAGGGAGUUGCCCAUCGCCGCCCUAGCAAGUCCAUUCCCACACGACCUUUCCAGUGGUGAUGAUGACAGUGGCCCAUACAGCUGACUGUUUGCAUCUCACGUUCACAUUGCUAGAGGUGAUGGGUGUGCUACACCCGUGGAAACAGGCUUCUGGCAUCUCAGUGUCUUUAUUUUAUUUUUGAGAUGGAGUUUCGCUCUUGUUGCCCAGGCUGGAGUGCAGUGGCGUGAUCUCAGCUCACUGCAACCUCCACCUACCGGGUUCAAGUGAUCCUCCUGCCUCGGCCUCCUGAAUAGCUGGGAUUACAGGCAUGCACCACCAUGCCCAGCUAAUUACUAUAUUUUUAGUAGAGACAGGGCUUCACCGUGUUGGCCAGGCUGGUCUCAAACUCCUGGCCUCAGCCAGUGAUCCUCCUGCCUCAGCCUCCCAAAGUGCUGAGAUGACAGGCAUGAGCCACUGCACCUGGCCAAAUUUUUGUAUUUUUUGUAGAGAUGGAAUCUCGCUAUUUUCCCUGGGCUGGUCUCAAACUCCUGGCAUUAAGGGCUCCUCCUAUCUCAGCCUCUCAAAGUGCCGGGGUUCUAGGUGUGAGUCACCGAGUUGAGCCCCUAAACACAUGUUUUUCUUUUUAGAGACAGGGUCUCACUCGGUUGCCCAGGCUGGAGUGCAGUGGCGUGACCAUGGCUCACUGCAGCCUCAACCUCCCGGGCUCAAGUGAUCCUCCCACCUCAGCCUUCUGAGCAGCUGGGACCACAGACACACACCACCAUGUCGGCUAAUUUUUGUAUCUUUUGUAGAGACAAGGUUUCACCAUGUUGCUCGGGCUGGUCUCGAACUCCUGAGCUCAAGUGGUCCUCCCACCUUGGCCUCCCAAAAUGCUGGGAUUACAAGUGUGAGCCACCACACCCAGCCCCUAAAAACAUUUAUGUGCAUCGACAUCAGCUUUGAUCAGAAGAGCCCCUGCUCCUCUUGGGCUGGGACCCCUUCCUGGACUGAGUCUGCUCACCUUGGAUUAGGCCACCUACUGCUUCUUCCUCUUCCUUUUCUCAGGCUCUGCAAGGAAGAGCUCCAGCUUCCUCUUGGAGAAGGAGAUUCUGGGCCCCUUUUCUCUCUCCCAAACCUAGGUGGUGGCCAUGCCCCUCGAGCUCUGCUUGGCACGUGUCUGCCAGUCUCAGGGGGCUCCAUGGGAGUGAGGAAGGGCUCGGCGGCCCUGGGGGUCUGGUCCUCCUCCGCCAUCCUCGAGUCCUCGGGCUACGUGCCCUCAUCUUUGGCUUCCAGGGACACGGGCCCAGCUGGCCACUUCUAUGACAAGAAUGUGGGUUUUUUGUGACAGGGCGUCUACUAUAUGAACUUCCUCUGGACUCUGACUUCAGUGUGUAGGAAGCCACCUUACAGCUCAUGUCACCCAGAGAACAGUCGUUGCAGCUCCAGUUGGAAUGACUGGGGGUGUCUUCCGAAUCGCCAUCAUAAAGAUCUAAAAGCUGAGGACAAAAGUGUUUCUCAGUCCAAGAGCAGUUCUGCGAGGCGGAAUCAAGUCUAACAUGCUCGCAUGCGCUGACUCUUCCUCCCGUCACUGAUGCUGGUUUUUGCAGGCUCUGCCUUGCAAAUGAAUUUUUCUUUCUUUUUUUUUUUUUUUUUGAGACGGAAUCUUGCUCUGUCGCCCAAGCUGGAGUGCAGUGGCGCAAUCUGGGCUCACUGCAACCUCCACCUCCCGGAUUCAAGCGAUUCUCCUGCCUCAGCCUCCUGAGUAGCUGGGACUACAGGCGCCCGCUAAUUUUUGUAUUUUUAGUAGAGACGGGGUUUCACCAUAUUGGUCAGGCUGGUCUUGAACUCCUGACUCAGGUGAUCCACCCGCCUCAGCCUCCCAAGGUGCUGGGAUUACAGGUGUGAGCCACCACGCCUGGCCGAAUUUUUAUUUGUUUUUUGUUUGUUUUUGUUUUUUUUAAAAAACUGAGUCUCGCACUGUUGUCCAGGCUGGAGUGCAGUGGCGCGAUCUCGGCUCACUGCAAGCUCCGCCUCCCAGGUUCACGCCAUUCUCCUGCCUCAGCCUCCCAAGUAGCUGGGACUACAGGCGCCCACCACCAAGCCCGGCUAAUUUUUUGGAUUUUUAGUAGAGACAGGGUUUCACUGUGUUAGCCAGGAUGGUCUCGCUCUCCUGACCUCGUGAUCCACCCGCCUCCCAAAGUGCUGAGAUUACAGGCGUGAGCCACCACACUCGGCCUCUUUGUUUGUUUUUUUUUUUUUUUGAGACAGUCUGGCUCUGUCACUGAGGCUGGAGUGCAGUGAUGCAACCUCAUCUCACUGCAGCCUAGACCUCCUGGGCUUAAGUGAUCCUCCCACCUCAGCCUCCCCAGACUACAGGUGCACACCACCACGCCCGGCUAAUUUUUGUAUUUUUUGUAGAGAUGGAGUUUCGCCAUGUUGCCCAGGAUGGCCUUGAACUCCAGGGCUCAAGCAAUCCACCCACCUCAACCUCCCAAAGUGCUGGGAUUACAGGCAUGAGCCAUUGUGCCCAGCUGCAAAUGAAUUUUUAAAAAUGUGUUAGAUCAAUAUUCAUAUCACCCAAAAACAGCCUGAGAGCCCGCCACCACUGGGGACUCAGCCUGAGCCUUGUUCCCAGAAAGCCCUCAACGCAGUGCUGGGCACAGACCUGGGAGGCUUGGCUCAAACCGCCCUGCCCUCCGUUGGCAGGGCAGAGCUCCGUCUUUUCCUCUCAACAGCUCUUCCAAAGGGCAAGGCAGCAUUUUCCUGGUGAGGGGCAAGCGAAGCUGAGGCCAGACCCACCCCCGAGUCUUCCCUCUGCCACAUCCAGGGCCUGAAGGGCGUUCUGGGGAGCCUCCACCUUCACACCGAAGGCCGCCAAGGUGGUUGGCAAGAAGCUGAAAUGGGCGUUUAAGUCCGAACCUUGUUUUCAAAGGUGCCCAUUGCCUGUUCUCAAAGCAAUGCACCUGAGAAGCAGUGGCAGGUGGCACAGCCCACCCCCAACCGCCAGGGCCACCCAAACACCAGUUACAACACCAUCACCAACAGAGCCUUUGCAGAACUUUUUUUUUUUUUUUUUUUUUUGAGACGGAGUCUUGCUCUGUCGCCCAGGCUGGAGUGCAAUGGUGUGAUCUUGGCUGACUGCAACCUCCGCCUCCCAAGUUCAAAUGAUUCUCCUACCUCAGCCUCCCAAGCAGCUGGGACUACAGGCACCCACCACCAUGCCCGGCUAAUUUUUCUAUUUUUAGUAGAGACAGGGUUUUGCCAUGUUGCCCAGGCUGGUCUCGAACUCCUGACCUCAGGUGAUCUGCCCACCUUGGCCUCCCAAAGUGCUGGGAUUACAGGCAUGAGCCACCACUCCUGGCCCUCUUGUAUUUUUUUGUAGAGACAGGGUUUUGCCAUGUUGCCCAGGCUGGUCUCCUGGGCUCAAGUGAUCCACCCACCUUGGUCUCCCAAAGUGCUAGGAUUAUGGGCCUGAGCCACCCCACCCGGCCCAACCUUAUUAUUACUGAAGUCGCCUUGUUACACACAAACAUCUACAGUGCCUCCUGGCCACUCCUUCUGGACUUUUCUUUCCUAGCCCAGGUCAAAGUGGGCCUUCGGGAGGACCCUGGAGGAGAAGCCCCCUCCUCUUCACUUCCACCCUCUCUCUUCCACCCCUGGAAGUCAGCUUUCUGACCUCAGAAUCCCAGCUAUCUUCUGGACUCAGGUGACAAGUCACCUAAGUGACAGAUCCAGCAUGCACUUUAUGACCAUCACUCUGCUCCUCCUGCAUCAGCGCCCCACCCAACAGAGCCGACCAGGCUGGGAACACCGAGACCGAGAGCGCGUGGCUGUGUCUACAAAGGCCUCCUCUUUGAGGGAGACACGCGAGGCACGGGUGGGGCGAUGAGACAGGAUCGGCCGGUCCUUGACAGUCUCUGAAGCUGGGAGAACAUGACCCCAUGCUCUCCUGUUGGAGUCACCACCUCUUUGCCAACAGCCACCAAACCUCCACCUCCAAUUAAGCUCCACCCCCAUGUCCCCACUGCCCUCCGGACAUCUGUUCAGCACCCCCCUCGACCUGGCCAAGGCUCCACGCACCGCCCUGGUUUCCCGCUCUGCCCAGCCCCCCGCUGAAGUCUCUAAUGGGUUCUUCCGAUUCCACCUGUCCAAGGUAAAACCCUGAGGUUGUCCCUCCUCCGCGGCACCUCCAGGUAUCUGGUUGCUCAGGCUGAAAUGUUUCCCAAGGCCCUGGCUCCUCCUCCUUCCAAACCCCGCAGGCAGCUGAUUAGCAAACUCUGACUCUAACCUCAAAACAUGUCCAGAAUUCAGCCACAUCUCCCCACUUCCCCGCCUGGCCCUGGGCCCCGCUAUUCCAUCUCAAUCUCUGCCCUGGCCCCCAGCCCAGCAUCCACUCUCAGACCAGAGCAAUGCUUGUGAACUCCGAAAAUCUGAGACAGGUCUCAGUUAAUUUAGAAAAGAUAUUUGUCAAGGUUGAGGACGCGCACCCAUGACACAGCCUCAGGAGGUCCUGACUGGGGGGAGAGAGACCCUCUCAUAUUGUUUUAUACUCAGUACCUGUUUUAAGAAAAAAACGAAGUGAAAUCAAAGACAGGCAGCCCGGCGCCAGGCCCAAAACCAGGCCUGGGCCUGCCUGGCCUAAACCUAGUCGUUAAAAAUCAGCUCAUGACUUAGAACCCGAUGUUACCCAUAGAUUUCAGGCAUUGUAUGGAAGAACAUCGUGAGACUCCCUGCUCUGUUCUGUUUCACUCUGACUACCAGUGCAUGAAACCCCUGUCACGUAUCCCCCAGACUGCUCAAUCAAUCACGACCCUUUCACGUAAAAUCUUUAGUGUUGUGAGCCCUUAAAAGGGACAGAAAUUGUGCACUUGGGGAGCUGGGAUUUUAAGAUGGUAACUUGCCGAUGCUCCCAGCUGAAUAAAGCCCUUCCUUCUACAA